ACACUCGCCUCACAUUCCCCCACAGUCACAUUGCGCUCUGUGAUUCUGAGGAAUACAGUGUGCCAGCAUCCGAUCCAGUCUCCUUUCACCUGCAGGUGUUCCAGAAACUUCAAAAUGCGUCUGGAAGAACUGAAAAGAUUGCAGAAUCCUCUAGAACAAGUUAAUGAUGGAAAAUAUUCAUUUGAAAAUCACCAGCUGGCCAUGGAUGCAGAGAAUAAUAUUGAAAAGUAUCCCCUCAAUCUACAGCCCUUGGAAUCAAAGGUGAAAAUCAUUCAGCGAGCAUGGCGAGAGUACCUGCAGCGGCAGGAGCCCCUGGGGAAGAGGAGCCCGUCCCCACCCUCUGUCUCCUCAGAGAAGCUGAGCAGCUCUGUCAGCAUGAACACCUUCUCCGACAGCAGCACACCCGAUUACCGAGAGGAUGGGAUGGAUCUAGGCAGUGACGCCGGCAGCAGCAGCAGCAGCAGCCGCGCCAGUUCACAGUCCAACUCCACCAAAGUGACCCCUUGCUCCGAGUGCAAAUCUUCAUCGUCGCCGGGGGGCAGCCUGGACUUGGUGUCUGCCCUGGAGGACUAUGAGGAGCCCUUCCCGGUCUACCAGAAGAAGGUGAUUGAUGAGUGGGCGCCGGAGGAGGACGGGGAGGAGGAGGAAGAGGAGGACGAGCGCGACCAGCGAGGGUACCGGGAUGACCGCUCUCCGGCCCGGGAACCGGGGGACGUAAGCGCCAGGACCCGCAGCGGCGGCGGCGGGGGCAGGAGCGCCACCACCGCCAUGCCGCCCCCGGUGCCCAACGGCAACCUCCACCAGCACGACCCCCAGGACCUCAGGCACAAUGGCAACGUGGUGGUGGCUGGCCGGCCGAGCUGUUCCCGGGGCCCCCGCCGGGCGAUCCAAAAGCCCCAGCCGGCUGGGGGCCGGCGCAGUGGCCGCGGCCCGGCGGCUGGGGGGCUCUGCCUUCAGCCCCCAGACGGCGGGACGUGCGUCCCCGAAGAGCCCCCGGUGCCACCUAUGGAUUGGGAGGCGCUGGAGAAGCAUCUGGCCGGGCUGCAGUUCCGGGAGCAGGAGGUACGGAACCAGGGCCAGGCGAGGACCAACUCCACCUCCGCACAGAAAAAUGAGAGAGAGUCUAUCAGACAGAAGUUGGCACUUGGAAGCUUCUUUGAUGAUGGCCCAGGAAUUUAUACCAGCUGUAGCAAAAGUGGGAAGCCAAGCCUUUCCUCCCGACUGCAGAGUGGGAUGAACUUGCAGAUAUGCUUUGUCAACGACAGUGGCAGUGAUAAGGACAGUGAUGCUGAUGACAGUAAGACUGAAACCAGCUUGGACACCCCCUUGUCUCCCAUGAGCAAACAGAGUUCUUCCUAUUCUGAUAGAGACACUACUGAAGAGGAGUCUGAAUCCUUGGAUGACAUGGACUUCCUUACAAGGCAAAAGAAAUUGCAAGCUGAAGCCAAAAUGGCCCUUGCCAUGGCCAAACCAAUGGCCAAAAUGCAAGUAGAAGUGGAGAAACAGAACAGGAAAAAGUCUCCCGUCGCUGAUCUUCUGCCACACAUGCCUCAUAUAAGUGAAUGCUUGAUGAAAAGAAGUUUAAAACCCACCGACCUGAGAGACAUGACUAUUGGGCAGCUACAAGUGAUAGUCAAUGAUCUCCAUUCCCAGAUAGAAAGCUUGAAUGAAGAGUUGGUCCAGCUGCUUCUCAUCCGAGAUGAGCUGCACACAGAGCAGGAUGCCAUGCUGGUGGACAUUGAAGACUUGACCAGACAUGCUGAAAGUCAGCAGAAGCACAUGGCAGAGAAAAUGCCUGCAAAGUGAAAAGAAGCCAUUCAACCAGAGAACAAGCUAGAAUUUAUUUUGCUUCUGUGGUUGUAAAAAUGCUGUUGCUAAAGGUGGCGCAGAAACAAAUAUCAGUGUUAGUCAUUGAUAAUGUCUGAAGCUUAAUGUCCAGUGAUUGGCCUUUGCUUCUUAAUUUAUUUUAAUUUUUUACUUGUGCCACUUAAUAUCAGGCAUUUUAAUAAAAUAUUGUUACAAAAAAUGUACAGUACUGACACCACCACAAAUCAUGGUUAAUAAAAGAGAGUAGUUUUAACUUUAUUUUUAUUUGUUUAGAGAUUUUAAGUUGGAACAGUAUUUUCCCAUUGACUACUUUUCAUUCUUCACUGUAGUUUUAAAGAAGAACUGUAAAUGACGGUGCUAUACAAGUCAAAAAAUACAUGCCUGCCUCGUAGUGAAGUUGUAGCUCUCCGUAAUAUGUAUAUUUUACUCAGUUUUCAACAUUUUGUGAAUGUUGACUACCUGAAGUUCCUUUUUAGAUGUGCUAUUAACAUUCUGUUGGAUUCAGAGGGUUCCUUGAAAGUUUUAUGUAUAAAUAUGUAAAAUAAAAAUUAAAACUUUGUUUCA